UCCGAGGGCAAUUUCUUGAAAAUUAAUUAAUUCCGUUUCUUUAUUACCUGUGGAGUCACCAUGUCUCUUUGCACCCGCUGUUCUCUCUACCUGGGAACCUUCUCCCAUUUUCUCCCUGUGGAAUGCCUAUUUGUUUACAGGUCUAGGUCAAAUGUCAGGUCAUCUGGGAUCCUUUCCUGAUCCUUUAGAUUUCAUUGUUCAUUCCAUUGCAUUCCCACCGUGUGCGGCAUUGUUCUCCACUUAAUUUUUAUUUCAUGUAUGUUGUUUAUAGGUCUGUGCUCCAAUACGUAUUUUUUCCCUUUAAGGGCAAGAAUCCUAUCUUAGUUAUCUAUCUCCCCAAAACUACCGGUGUAUCUUAUACUUUGGUGGCAGUAAAUGACUCUGUAAGAAUUAAAUCCAAGGCAGCAUGUUAACAGAAAAAGCUAACAUUUAACAGGAGCUUCCUGUAUAUCAGAUACUAUGCUAAAAGAUUUAUGUUUAUUAACUCAUACAGUUCUCAAAACCACCUACUUUUUUUUUUUAUGAUCCCCAUUUUACAGAUGAGGAAAUUGAAGAUUAGAGAGGUUACAUUGCUUACCCAAGGCCACACUAUGAAAUGGUGGAGCUGGGAUUCAAACUCUUGUUCCUAAUCACUAUACCAUGUCUAUUUAUAACAAAAAGACACCAUCAAAUGAGACAAAUGAGAACACAGAUAAGCCUGAGCACAGAUGAAGAGCUUCCAGAAAAAUACACCCAGCGUCGCAGGCCGUGGCUCAGCCAAUUGUCAAAUAAGAAGCAAUCCAACACGGGCCGUGUGCAGCCGUCAAAACGAAAGCCACUGCCUCCCCUCCCACCCUCUGAGGUUGCUGAAGAGAAGAUCCAAGUCAAGGCACUUUAUGAUUUUCUGCCCAGAGAACCCUGUAAUUUAGCCUUAAGGAGAGCAGAAGAAUACCUGAUACUGGAGAAAUACAAUCCUCACUGGUGGAAGGCAAGAGACCGUUUGGGGAAUGAAGGCUUAAUCCCAAGCAACUAUGUGACUGAAAACAAAAUAACUAAUUUAGAAAUAUAUGAGUGGUACCAUAGAAACAUUACCAGAAAUCAGGCAGAACAUCUAUUGAGACAAGAGUCUAAAGAAGGUGCAUUUAUUGUCAGAGAUUCAAGACAUUUAGGAUCCUACACAAUUUCCGUAUUUAUGGGAGCUAGAAGAAGUACGGAGGCUGCCAUAAAACAUUAUCAGAUAAAAAAGAAUGACUCAGGACAGUGGUAUGUGGCUGAAAGACACGCCUUUCAAUCAAUCCCUGAGUUAAUCUGGUAUCACCAGCACAAUGCAGCCGGUCUCAUGACUCGUCUCCGAUAUCCAGUUGGGCUGAUGGGCAGUUGUUUACCAGCCACAGCUGGGUUUAGCUACGAAAAGUGGGAGAUAGAUCCAUCUGAGUUGGCUUUUAUAAAGGAGAUUGGAAGCGGUCAGUUUGGAGUGGUCCAUUUAGGUGAAUGGCGGUCACAUAUCCAGGUAGCUAUCAAGGCCAUCAAUGAAGGCUCCAUGUCUGAAGAGGAUUUCAUUGAAGAGGCCAAAGUGAUGAUGAAAUUAUCUCAUUCAAAGCUAGUGCAACUUUAUGGAGUCUGUAUACAGCGGAAGCCCCUUUACAUUGUGACAGAGUUCAUGGAAAAUGGCUGCCUGCUUAACUAUCUCAGGGAGAAUAAAGGAAAGCUUAGGAAGGAAAUGCUACUGAGUGUAUGCCAGGAUAUAUGUGAAGGAAUGGAAUAUCUGGAGAGGAAUGGCUAUAUUCAUAGGGAUUUGGCGGCAAGGAAUUGUUUGGUCAGUUCAACAUGCAUAGUAAAAAUUUCAGACUUUGGAAUGACAAGGUACGUUUUGGAUGAUGAGUAUGUCAGUUCUUUUGGAGCCAAGUUCCCAAUCAAGUGGUCCCCUCCUGAAGUUUUUCUUUUCAAUAAGUACAGCAGUAAAUCUGAUGUCUGGUCAUUUGGAGUUUUAAUGUGGGAAGUUUUUACAGAAGGAAAAAUGCCUUUUGAAAAUAAGUCAAAUUUGCAAGUCGUGGAAGCUAUUUCUGAAGGCUUCAGGCUAUAUCGCCCUCACCUGGCACCAAUGUCCAUAUAUGAAGUCAUGUACAGCUGCUGGCAUGAGAAACCUGAAGGCCGCCCUACAUUUGCCGAGCUGCUGCGGGCUGUCACAGAGAUUGCGGAAACCUGGUGACCGGAAACAGAAUGCCAACCCAAAGAGUCAUCUUGCAAAACUGUCAUUUAUUGUGAAUAUCUUCACCAUAUGGGGUCACUUAUGGUGAAUAUCUUUCUUCAGAGUUGCUGACUCUUGAAAACAGUGCAAAGAUCACAGUUUUUAAAAGUUUUAAAAAUUUAAGAAUAUUCACACAAUCGUUUUUCUAUGUGUGAGAGGGAUUUGCACACUCUUAUUUUUCUGUAAAAUAUUUCACAUCCCAAAUGUGAAGAAGUGAAAAAGACUUCGCAGCAGUCUUCAUUGUGGUGCUCUUCAUGAUCAUAGCCCCAGGAACCCUUGAGGUUCUUCUUCACAAGGCUGAGAGUGCUUCCUUCUUGAAGACGAGUGACAUUCAUCACUUCAGUGAUCCAUGCAUAGAAUAUGAAAAUAAAUUCUUCCAACUCAUGGGAUAAAGGGGACUCCCUUGAAGAAUUUCAUGUUUUUGGGCUGUAUAGCUCUUUACAGAAAAUGCACCUUUAUAAAUCACAUGAAUGUUAGUAUUCUGGAAAUGUCUUUUGUUAAUAUAAUCUUCCCAUGUUAUUUAACAAAUUGUUUUUGCACAUAUCUGAUUAUAUUGAAAGCAGUUUUUUGCAUUCGAGUUUUAAACACUGUUAUAAAAUGUAGCCAAAGCUCACCUUUGAACAGAUCCCGGUGACAUUCUAUUUCCAGGAAAAUCCGGAACCUGAUUUUAGUUCUGUGAUUUUACACUUUUUACAUGUGAGAUUGGACAGUUUCAGAGGCCUUAUUUUGUCAUACUAAGUGUCUCCUGUAAUUUUCAGGAAGAUGAUUUGUUCUUUCCAGAAGAGGAGACAAAAGCAAGAUAGCCAAAUGUGACAUCAAGCUCCAUUGUUUCGGAAAUCCAGGAUUUUGAAUUCGAGAUGAAACAACCAGCAAUCACAGUUAAAUCUUAACUUUGCCUGCACUCUUUGUAGGAAUGAUCAGAAAUUUAUCUUUAUCAUUCUGAGUGCUUCAGGAGUACAAUAGGAAGAAAGAUACUGGAGAAAGCACUAAUGUAAUCACCAUGAAGUCUGACAACAGGAGCCCAUUAUUUGCGUACUGUCCCACCCUGUAUCAUGGUUCUCUGGGAACAAGCUUUAUGAUUCUCAUUAGAGUUUAUUUGUUGAUUGUCAGUAGUUGCGACUUUUAAAUUAUAUUUCCCCCACUCAAAGAAUGGUAUCUUUAUAUAUCAAUGACAUUCAAUAAAUGUGUAUUAUUUCUAAUGAGAA